AAUCAUUAAACACGAAACGAGCCUCUGACCUUGCCCUGUUGGCAUUUCUACUGGCCAGAGAAAUACAACUUAAAGAAGAACAUAUAAGGGUUUGAUGGAAAAUAGAUUUCCAAACACGCCCAACCUGCCAAACAGGAAUAAAAGCUUCCAGUGGAAGCAUCACGUUCCCUUGAAAUAGAAGUGUUUUAGCUUGUGUGAGCGUAUUUGACUCUUGAAAAGAAAUGAGAUCGUGUUUCAUUUCAGGAAGAUAUAUGCGUCAGGAAAAUUUCUAUCUUCUUUUGUAUUAUCAAGGAGAUAUUUGGAGCAGAGUCAACCCUCUCAGUUACAUAAAAUAAAAAAUGGCAUAUUCUUGGCAAACGGAUCCAAAUCCUAAUGAAUCACACGAAAAGCAGUAUGAACACCAAGAAUUUCUCUUUGUAAAUCAACCCCAUUCUUCUAGCCAAGUCAGUCUGGGUUUUGAUCAGAUAGUAGAUGAGAUCAGUGGCAAAAUUCCACACUACGAGAGUGAAAUUGAUGAAAACACCUUUUUUGUGCCCACUGCACCAAAAUGGGACUCAACAGGGCAUUCAUUAAAUGAAGCACACCAAAUAUCCUUGAAUGAAUUCACUUCUAAAAGCCGUGAACUCUCCUGGCAUCAAGUUAGCAAAGCACCAGCAAUUGGUUUUAGUCCUUCUGUGUUACCAAAACCUCAAAAUACGAAUAAAGAAUGCUCCUGGGGAAGCCCCAUAGGAAAACAUCAUGGUGCUGAUGAUUCCAGAUUCAGUAUUUUAGCUCCAUCAUUCACAAGUUUGGAUAAAAUUAAUCUAGAGAAAGAAUUAGAAAAUGAAAAUCAUAACUACCAUAUAGGAUUUGAAAGUAGCAUUCCUCCAACAAAUUCAUCCUUCUCAAGUGACUUCAUGCCGAAAGAAGAGAAUAAAAGGAGUGGACAUGUGAACAUUGUGGAACCAUCUUUGAUGCUUUUGAAAGGCUCUCUUCAACCCGGAAUGUGGGAAAGUACAUGGCAGAAGAAUAUAGAGUCAAUAGGUUGUUCCAUUCAGCUAGUGGAAGUACCUCAAAGCAGCAAUACGAGUCUGGCCUCUUUUUGCAACAAAGUAAAAAAAAUCAGAGAAAGAUAUCAUGCAGCUGAUGUUAAUUUCAAUUCUGGGAAGAUCUGGAGCACUACUACAGCAUUUCCGUAUCAGCUCUUUUCUAAGACCAAGUUUAAUAUACAUAUUUUUAUUGAUAACUCAACACAACCUCUUCAUUUUAUGCCAUGUGCUAAUUAUCUUGUCAAAGAUCUAAUUGCAGAAAUUCUGCAUUUUUGCACAAAUGACCAGCUACUCCCCAAAGAUCAUAUUCUAAGUGUAUGUGGCUCUGAAGAAUUUUUACAAAACGACCACUGUUUGGGGAGCCACAAAAUGUUUCAAAAAGAUAAAUCUGUUAUUCAGCUCCACCUGCAGAAAAGUAGGGAAGCUCCAGGAAAGCUAUCUCGAAAGCAUGAAGAGGACCACAGUCAGUUUUAUCUGAAUCAACUUCUAGAAUUUAUGCAUAUUUGGAAAGUAUCCAGACAAUGUCUCUUAACACUCAUCAGAAAAUAUGACUUCCACCUGAAAUACCUAUUGAAAACCCAGGAAAACGUGUAUAAUAUUAUUGAAGAAGUUAAAAAAAUAUGCAGUGUUCUAGGGUGUGUGGAAACCAAACAAAUUACAGAUGCAGUAAAUGAACUAAGUCUAAUUCUUCAGAGAAAAGGAGAGAAUUUUUAUCAAAGUUCAGAGACUUCAGCAAAAGGCUUGAUAGAGAAGGUAACAACUGAACUAUCCACAUCCAUCUACCAGCUAAUCAAUGUCUACUGUAACAGCUUUUAUGCAGAUUUUCAGCCUGUAAAUGUACCUAGAUGCACUUCCUAUCUAAAUCCCGGGCUUCCUUCCCACCUCAGCUUCACAGUGUAUGCAGCACACAACAUUCCAGAAACCUGGGUGCACAGCUACAAAGCGUUUUCUUUUACCUGUUGGCUUACAUAUGCUGGAAAGAAGCUGUGCCAAGUGAGAAACUACAGAAAUAUUCCAGACAAGAAAUUAUUUUUUUUCUUGGUCAACUGGAAUGAAACGAUCAAUUUUCCCCUUGAAAUAAAGUCACUUCCAAGGGAAUCCAUGCUCACUGUAAAACUGUUUGGGAUUGCCUGUGCAACCAACAAUGCAAAUUUACUGGCGUGGACUUGUCUUCCACUGUUUCCAAAAGAAAAAUCCAUUCUCGGGUCUAUGCUGUUCAGCAUGACAUUACAGAGUGAGCCUCCCGUAGAAAUGAUAACUCCAGGAGUGUGGGAUGUAAGUCAGCCAUCCCCGGUGACCCUGCAGAUUGAUUUUCCAGCUACUGGGUGGGAGUAUAUGAAACCUGAUUCUGAAGAGAAUAGAAGUAAUCUUGAAGAGCCACUAAAGGAGUGUAUAAAACAUAUUGCCAGACUUUCACAGAAACAGACUCCCCUACUACUCUCUGAAGAAAAGAAAAGAUAUUUAUGGUUUUAUCGCUUCUACUGCAAUAAUGAAAACUGCUCCCUUCCUUUAGUCCUGGGUAGUGCCCCUGGAUGGGAUGAAAGGACUGUUUCAGAAAUGCAUACCAUUUUGAGAAGAUGGACAUUUUCUCAACCUUUAGAGGCUCUUGGGCUUUUGACUUCCAGUUUUCCAGAUCAAGAAAUUCGUAAAGUGGCAGUUCAACAAUUAGACAACCUCUUGAAUGAUGAACUACUGGAAUAUCUCCCACAGCUAGUUCAGGCUGUCAAGUUUGAAUGGAACCUUGAGAGUCCUUUAGUGCAACUUCUACUCCACCGCUCCUUGCAGAGCAUCCAGGUUGCCCAUCGUCUUUACUGAAGAGACUACAGGAAGAAGCAUGUGCUUAAUGACCAGAAAAUGAGUCAAACCAUUGAUGUGAAACUGAGCAGCUUAAUUUUGUUGGUUAAUGGUGAGUAAUGCACAAAACAAGCCAAUGACUAAAAUAUAUCUUAGGGAGAAGAAAAAGACCAACAUGAUUUUAUUCCUCUGAAAUUAUAACAUCAUAAUCCAUCUUUGCAGCAAAAGGGUCUCUAGAAAUUAUUACACACAUUCCUUGAUCAUAUACCCAGAUUGCUUCAAUCAGCUAAUUAGACAAAGCCAUUGUAUAGUAUUUUCAAUCUUUAUUUCCAAAUCAGAGUUAAAUUUGCUUCCUACGUCAGUGUGACUGGCAGCUCCUCUGUCACCCUCAAUCUCUAAACUAUUGCUUCUAAUUUGGAGUUGCCUGAGAGACCCAUUUCUGAAAAGGAGGCUUUUACCUACAAAGCAGUUUAUAGCUUCUUUGAUUUCAGUGCAACAAAGCUUUCGACUCUGCUUAAAAUGGAAAUGAUUAUUUCUUACAGGAAAGAAACGAGUGAACCCCUGCUGGGGGGAAAAUGUUUUCUUGGAAAUACUUUUAUAAACUUGGUAAUUAAUGGCAGUAAAAUUGCUUAUUUAAAACUAUGACCUUUUCAAAGACAUGCUGAAUAUGCUCAAAUUAUCCUAUACUUGUAAUCAUUUUUCAAAUUGUAGUUGAAGUUUAUUUAAACUAUUAAAUAUACUACUCUGACUUUUGUCCUACGGAUGCUUAUCUUAGCCCCUCUGAAUAUUUUCUUACAACUAAUUUCCCCAAAUUUCUUCCACUCCUCAAAUUAUUCUUUCUCUCUCCCCUCCACUUCUCUUCCCUCCACAUUUGGUUUCUUAUAUUAUCUUUUGAUAUUACAUUUUAUUUUUCUCCACAAAAGAUGAAUGUAUGCUUAAUUCACCUGUGAAGUCUCUCUUUAAAAAAAAAAAAAAGCUUAUUACACACACUGGUUACUCUAAUACCAGAUAUCAGCACCCUCUUAUUACCUAGCUAUCUUCACUAAUUGUUUAAAGCUUGUCAAGUGUGGUAAAACAAAAUGCAGCCACCUGCUACUCUUUUUUUUUUUUUUCAUUUGGGUUUUAUGGCUUUCUGAGACUGGUAUUACCAACUUUGUCAUAGGCUUUAGAGUCAUAUCUAAAGUUUACCUGAGAGUUAAACUUCAGUAUACUUUAUUUCUUUAUCACAUUUUGCUAUUAUAUCUCCUCUUUUACUCCACACAUCCUUCUGCUUCUGACCACAGUGGGUGAUAGACUGCCAAUUUAAGGCAUAAUAUAGUAAACAAUUUGGGAGAUAUUAUUUAUAAUAAUAGUAUCAUGAGUGAAGGUAUGUGGCUGGCAAAGAAGCAGUUAAGAUUAUAACUGAUCUAGAUCUAGACCAGCAUUUGGGUUGAGUUAGUCAAGGCCAACCAGAAUAUUUUUCAAGGCUGCCCGUUAGCAGAAAAAGUCUUCAAGCCAGGAUACCAGUUCAAGGUAGGAAGACGCAGGGUCCAGGGUCUCUAAUACUUGGUCAGAGAGCUUUCAAGUAGAGACUUGCUAAUAACUUAGAGAUGCAUAUCCCAAACAUUUCUUCCAUGAAACCACAGCCCCAUGCGGUUAGGGCUUAGUGGUCAAAUAAAUCUGCAAAGGGCUGAAUGCUUUGUUCCAACCAUAGAAAGUUGUGCACUUUAAAAUGUGAAGAUGCUGAAAACUCCUGUGCUUUAGAACAAUUCAAUUUUUGUAGCUUUUCUCAAACCUAUUUGACCUAUUGACUGUCUUUGAAGGAAUACUCUUUGGAAACUAGAGCCUAGGAUGUAUCCUUGCCACCUCGUCUCUCAGCUUCAUAACUGGUCCCCAAGUUCUGUAAGCCACACGGUUCAUUCCUCAAAAAAUCCCUUGCAACUCUUCCUUCCUUCCAGCCACCACCCAUGUUCAUGUCAGUGGUUCUCAAUGUCAACAGAAGGGAGGAAAGAUGGAGAUAGUUCACAUCAACAGGAGAAUGUGUAGUUUCAAAAAUCAAAAUUAAAUAUUAUAACGUUUUAUUAUAAUGUUUUAUUAUAAUGUUUUAUUUAUCAUCAAACUAAUUUACUUUAUUUCAAAGUUUCCAAAAGAAUUAAAGGGAAUGAGAUUAAUUUUAUAUAUCCAAAGACAGAUUCAAUUUUAAAAAGUUAAGAAACGUUAACUUAGACCUUUAUGAUGCCCUAAGCAUCGAAUCAGACUUACUCUAAACUAUUUUUCUUCCCUCCAAUGUACCAGAGUCACCCUCAGCAAUGCAAUUAUCUGAAAAGAAACAAAUGAAAAAACUUGUACUCAUUUUGACAGACUUUCUGGUAUGCCAUAAAGAUGCCAGGGGAAGGAAAGCGAUGCUCCAGAAGGACCAGUUGCCUUACCUCAGACAAGACAAUUACUGCUAGGGACCUUAGUCUUCUCAUGUACAAAAUGGGCAUUCGGGAUUAGAGGAAUCUCAACCUACAUGAAUUCAACAUCUCCUCUCUACUCAAAAAUCUUGAAUGUAUAUAUACUGCUCUCCCCGGUGCUACCUAUAGAACAAAUCUACCUUUUGGCUUAGGUAUUUAAGACCUUCCAAAUCUAUUACAAAUCUAUCUUUGUAACCUUUUCACUAAUCCUCACCAUUAACUUUCUGCUCUUGUCCAAUUUUUCAGGUAACUGUUGCCUGAAUAAUUCUUGCUUGUUCUCAUCACAAAGCCUUGGCUUAUGACAGUCUUAUCUCUGGAAACUUCCUUACUACUUAUUUCUUUUCCAACACCUACCCAUCCAUAUCUUAUUUUUUUAGGAUUCAAUUCACAGAGCACAUUCCCCUGUGAACUUUCUACAAUUAUUCUGAACAAUGGUAAUUUCUUCCUAACUGAUUUUCUGUACCAAAAAAAUUUAUACUAUUAUUUGAUCCUUAUAAUGUAAGAUCUUGUGUAUUUAAGUAUGUUUUAUUUCUUCCAAUUAAGUUGUGUGAGUGCCUCUGGGGCUAGAAAUUUUUAUGCUUCAAUGGCUUUCUCAUAAUGCUUAGUAACAUGUUACCCAUAGUCAAUAAUCAAUAUUUAUUAAACUUUGGAUAUUAAUUAAUAAUGAAAGAUCUGUAGAUUCAUAAUAGAUUCCAUUUAUAUCAAAUUAGAUACUGCAUUACAAAAAUCAGAAUGGAAUACUCUUAGUAGGCUGUGAGAAAUUUGGUUCUAUUAUUUUAAACUACUACACUGAACUUUCUCAGUCACCUAAAUUAUCCAAAAUGGAAACUAAAUUCAAUUUCUUUGUAUCUUCAAAUUUGAAAGGACUUUCUACUUUUCUUGAUUCAAAAAUAUGUUCAAAUGUAUAAAAACAGGAAAAGAAGAAACAGAUUAAGCAGAAAUUCAAUUAAUUCAAGAAGUGAUCAUAAUGAUACAUUUAUAAUUCUUUCACUUUUGCUUAACAUAUCUUUAUGUUAAAAUCAUCACAUCUUAGAAAGAAAACAUCUAUAAAUAUUUUAUUAGUAUUUUUUGGACUCUGGAUUUGUGUCCAAAGACGUUCUUUAACUAGCUGUACUUAUCAGCUACCUAAAAGUCCUGUCCCAAUCAUGUUAUAUCACAUUUUUAACUUGUCUGCUUAUUCAUUUUUGUAUGUUUACUGUCUCCCUCUCCCUACUCCCAACUAUAAUGUAAGCUCUGUGACCACAUGAACUCUGGUCAUCACGAUCACCCUCAUGAUCAGUAAAGUCUUAGUCACUUCGCUGUAUUGUCAGGGUUUGUGUAGGCAUUUAGUAUUAUAUACAUUCAUUGAAUAAAUAAAAUACUUGCCUGAACUACAGCAAAUAAUUUUUUCUCUCUUGGCUUCAAUUGUUGCCCCUCUAAAAAUAGAAAAGUUUAUCUAUUCCAAUAUUUUUAUUAUUAUUAUUUGGAGACAAAGUCUCACUCUGUCACCCAGGCUGGAGUACAGUGGUGUGAUCUUGGCUCACCGCAACUUCCACCUCCUGGGUUCAAGCAAUUCUCCCACCUAAGCUUCCCGAGUAGCUGGGAUGACAGGCACCCGCCACCACGCCCAGCUAAUUUUUGUAUUUUUAGUAGAGAGGCGGUUUCACCAUGUUGGCCAGGCUGGUCACAAACUCCUGACCUCUGGUAAUCCACCCACCUCACCUUCCAAAAGUACUAGGAUUACAGGCGUGAGCCGUCGCGCAUGGCCUAUUUUGAUGUUUUUUAAAAAUGUGUUUCUCCAAAUCACAAGGUUCAUUAGAGCUCUCUCAGAGUGUGAAAGGGGAAACCAAAACAAGCAGUGGUCUAGGCUGCCUACUGCCCUCUCAGUAGGGCAAAUCGUUUUUUAUCCUGGGGGUGCAUGUUGAGGAAGGAAGAUGGUUCUAAGUAAGAUUUUGCUUUUACAAUGUUUUAAAGAAACUUCUAAACUAGAUUAUUUCCAUAGAUCUUUCCAGAGUCCAGGUCUGAUUUACAGAUUAUGUUUGUAGGUUUGUUUUUGUUAUUGUUGUUGUUUAAUUUCACAUGCUUGGAAAAA